AGGGAGUGUGGCACUGAGCCGGCUCAGGCAGAGACGCGGCACCAUGGCUAGCAAGAAAGUCUGCAUUGUAGGCUCCGGGAACUGGGGCUCAGCCAUCGCCAAGAUCGUGGGUGGCAAUGCAGCCCAGCUGGCACAGUUUGACCCACGGGUGACCAUGUGGGUAUUUGAGGAAGACAUUGGAGGCAAAAAGCUGACUGAGAUCAUCAACACGCAGCAUGAGAAUGUCAAAUACCUGCCAGGGCACAAGUUGCCCCCAAAUGUGGUGGCUGUCCCAGAUGUGGUCCAGGCUGCAGAGGAUGCUGACAUCCUGAUCUUUGUGGUGCCCCAUCAGUUCAUCGGCAAGAUCUGUGACCAGCUCAAGGGCCAUCUGAAGGCAAACGCCACUGGCAUAUCUCUUAUUAAGGGGGUAGACGAGGGCCCCAAUGGGCUGAAGCUCAUCUCGGAAGUGAUUGGGGAGCGCCUCGGCAUCCCCAUGAGUGUGCUGAUGGGGGCCAACAUUGCCAGCGAGGUGGCUGAUGAGAAGUUCUGUGAGACAACCAUUGGCUGCAAGGACCCGGCCCAGGGACAACUCCUGAAAGAGCUGAUGCAGACACCAAACUUCCGUAUCACAGUGGUGCAAGAGGUGGACACAGUAGAGAUCUGUGGAGCCUUAAAGAAUGUAGUGGCCGUGGGGGCUGGCUUCUGUGAUGGCCUGGGCUUUGGCGACAACACCAAGGCGGCAGUGAUCCGGCUGGGACUCAUGGAGAUGAUAGCCUUCGCCAAGCUCUUCUGCAGUGGCCCUGUGUCCUCUGCCACCUUCUUGGAGAGCUGUGGUGUUGCUGACCUGAUCACUACCUGCUAUGGAGGGCGGAACCGGAAAGUGGCUGAGGCCUUUGCGCGUACAGGAAAGUCCAUUGAGCAGCUGGAGAAAGAGUUGCUGAAUGGGCAGAAACUGCAGGGGCCCGAGACAGCCCGGGAGCUAUACAGCAUCCUCCAGCACAAGGGCCUGGUAGACAAGUUUCCCUUGUUCAUGGCUGUGUACAAGGUGUGCUACGAGGGCCAGCCAGUGGGUGAAUUCAUCCACUGCCUGCAGAAUCAUCCAGAACAUAUGUGAGUGGGGCCAGGGCCCAGGCCAGGCCGCUUUUUUACCCCAGUGGAGACCAGCAGAAGCCUGGGGUACCUAGUCACCAGGAUCUCCAGGACUCCCAGGGAGCAGAGUCUUCUCAUCUUUUCACUGGAGGACAGGAGGCUAUGGGGCCCAGCUACGCACCUGGAGAUCCUGAACUGUCAAGCCACUGGCAGCCUCAUGCCACCACAUUUGCCAGAAAUGCAGUUGCCCUGUCCCUCUCCAGAUGUGGGGCUUUCUCCAUAUCCUCUGGGAGGGGUGGAAUCAAGCCCCAGUGCUGCCUGCUUGGUGGCGGGGGUGAUGUAUGUGGAGAAGGGUUGGGGGAGAGGCCGGUAGGGCAGGGGCUGCUAGUGGCUGUCUCACAUACACCAGUAAUCCUGUUAAAGGGCUGAAGAAGUAUCUUAGCCACAGGAGCGAUGAGGCAAGGAUUGUCAGGGAGGGGUCUGGGCUUCUGAGCUGAUGCAGGCCCCAAGGACCCCUUUGCUGACCUCUGCCAGGACCCACACAGCUUCGAUGGAUCUCAGUGUUUGUUAACAAAAUACAAAGAUCUCAAACAAACCCCUUUUAGCUUCUCCUAGCAACAUCUGUGUCCUCAGAAACCUCUGGUUCUCCCCCUUCCCCCUCCCCCAGGCUGCCCUGGCACCCAAAUUGCUGCCAUGCUGGCAUCUGUAGCUCGGUGGCUUGACAUUCUCCCCAGGGACUUCCCGGUUCCUAGUUCUUUGCCAGCUCCUCCCCACUCUGUGCGACCUUUCCAAGCCUUCCCUCACCCUCCCCGCCAGCACCCUCUUUGGGGAGCAGGAACUUAAUCUGCUGACAGAGCUACACCUUUCAUAACAGGCUCAGAUCACUCAGCUCCCUGUGACCUUUGUAUUCACCCAGGCUUCCUUCUCAGUAGCUCUAGCUGGGGGAGGUGUCAGCUGGGCCCCUCCUGUGCUAUCUCCCCAGAGGACAUCCCUGACUCCACCCCUUUCUUCCUCCCAAACUCUGCACCUCUUCCUCAGCUGCUCCAGACCGGCCAGGGUAACCAGCUAACCAUGCCUGGCAUCUGGAAGCCAGCAGGCCAGAGGGUGGCCCAAAGGCUGAUGAACGGUAGGGAAGGGUGAGCAGAUUCCUAUGUUGGUGGGCACCAAUAUUCCAAGGGCAGCUCUCUUUGCUGAAUGAGGGCCUUCUCGUGAGGUACUGACAACACCAGCAACUCGAGAGCUGGGAAACUCAAGGAGGAGGAAGAAAAUCAAAACCACCCUACUCCCUGGGGUGAGGAAAGAACAGGAGGGGAGGAGGAGGAGUGUGCUCUGCACUUGCCUUGCUCCAGGAUGGGGUGGCAGCAGAGGAAUGUCACAGGUCAGCAGCCUAGGCCUCCAGCUAUAAAUAGUCCGGAGGGCCCGAGAGGCUCCCGCCCGUCCAGCAGGGCUGUCAGCUUCCUGUGUGGCAGCACCUGGCACACUGGCUCUGGCCAGCAUUAUGCUAAAACCCUGUUACUCUCCAAUGAACCAGGGAGGCGGGCUCCUCUCUGCGCCUAUCCCUUGAGAAUUCUGUCUUACCAGUGAAGGGUGGGGCUGCCCAGAUCAGGCAGCAGGAGUGAGGGGCACAGUCACCCCAGGCCUUGCUGAGCCCAGGUCUGGGUACUGAGUGUCCAGAGCUGCCUCCCCAGGAGGUUAAGGUGGGGGCAAAGGGGAAGCUUCAAGCACUUUGCCUACUUUUGUUCACUCCCCAGUGCACUGUGACUCAGGCCUUCCCAUCAGGCCUAUUUGUCUACCCAAUAAAGCGUGUUUUUUCCAGAAA